AUAGAGAAUCUCGCUCUGUCGCCCAGGCAGGAAUGCAGUGGCUCGAUCUCAGCUCACUGCAACCUCCACCUCCUGGGUUCAAGCAAUUCUCCUGUCUCAGCCUCCCAAGUAGCUGGGACUACAGGUGUGCGCCACCACACGCGGUGAAUUUUUGUAUUUUUAGUAGAGAUGGGGUUUCACCAUAUUGGCCAGGCUGAUCUCGAACUCCUGACUUUGUGAUCUGCCCACCUUGGCCUCCCAAAGUGCUGGGUUUACAGACGUGAGCCACUGCGCCUGGCCAGAAGGAUGGUACUUUUAAAAUUAGUUUGGUGAUAUUAGACAGGAUGUUUUGGAUUGAGAAAAAGGGAUCAGCCAGAAGACUUACAGUAAUGCACAGACAUGAAAUAAUGUCUGAAAUAGUGGUGAUAGUAAGACAGGGAAAGAACUAAAGACUUCAUUGGGUUUUUUUGUUUGUUUUUGUUUUGAGACAGGGUCUCACUUUGUCACCCAGACUGGAGUGCAGUGGUGUGAUCUCAGCUCACUGCAACCUUCACCUCCCAGGUUCAGGCGAUUCUCCCACCUCAGCCUCCUGAGUAGCUGGGACUACAGGUGUGCGCCACCACACCCGGCCAAUUUUUGUAUUUUUUGGUAGAGAUGCAGUUUCACCACGUUGGCCAGGCUGGUCUUGAACUCCUGACCUCAAGUGAUACGCUUGCCUUGGCCUCCCAAAGUGCUGGGAUUACAGGCAUGAGCCACUGUACCCGGCCCUUCAUUGGUUUUUAAAAGUUUAAAUGUAAUACAUAUAAUGGCAAAAAAUUCAAACAGUAAGCAAGGCUACAUAUUAUAGUAUAUAUACAUAACAGUACAGAGUAGGGAUACAAGAAUAUGUAUUAUGAUAAAAAAUAUAUGUUGCAUAUAUUAUAUAUGUUAACCCAUGAUACAUCCCACCUUCUAACUUUCCACAUUCUAACACCUCUGAAAGUGGGAUGUAUCACUGUUAUCUAAUAUUCCAUAAAUACUCUACAUAUGGAGAGACAAUACAACAAAACAGUUAAAAGCUCAGCUCCAGAGCCUGUUUCCUCAUUUGUAAAAACAGAAUAAUAACAGUAUGUACUUCAUAGGUACAUAGGUACUUGAUAGGUAUUUAAUGCUUCUUGAGAGCAUUAAGAGAUGUAUUUCAUGGAAAGUGUUUAAUAUUCUGCCUGGCAGUAAAGACUAAAUUUUCUUCCCACUCCAGAUCUUGAUUCCUCUCCUUAGAGACAGCAGCUGUUACUGGUUUCUUUUAUGAUGUCUCUGUUGAGAUAUUUUGAUAGAAAAAGCAGUAAAAAAUGGAAACUGGCACAUUUCUAGAUUUUAUUGACUUUCUUAAGAACUUUGACAGAUCUGAAAUUUUACCCCAUUUGUAAGCUAACAAGUUAACCUGCCUCAGUUUCAUGGAUGCUGGCAGGAGGCAGCAUCCUGGGUCAGUAGGCAGCAUGAACUUCAUGUCAGUUCCCUUUGACAUUCAUAUCUCACGGUAAGGGAGGAGACCACCCCUCAUAUUGUCUUAUGCCCAAUUUCUGCCUCCAAAAAAAGAAGAAGUAAAAACUAAAAGGCAGAAAUGAAAUCCACAAGCAGAUAGCCCGGUGCCACACCCUGGGCCUGGUAAAGAUCAACCCCUGACCUAAUUGGUUAUUUAUAGAUUACAGACAUUGUAUAGAAAAGCACUGUGAAAAUCCCUGUCCUGUUCUGUUCCAUUCUACCCCCUGCUUGCUCAAUCGAUCACGACCCUCCCAAACAGACCCCCUUAGAGUUGUGAGCCCCUAAAAGGGACAGGAAUUGCUCACUUGGGGAGCUCGGUUGUUGGAGACAAGAGUCUUGCCGAAGCUCCCGGCUGAAUAAAGCCCUUCCUUCUCAGUGUCUGAGGGGUUUUGUCUGUGGCUUGUCCUGCUACAAUGGGAGUGACAUGGAACAGCCUAGGUGAGUGCUGUGCAUCACUGCUAAGGGACCUUGAGCUUGGGAAACCCUGUCUGUAAGAAAACUCACUCAACUUUUGCCCCAGGAGAAGGUAUUUUAUACAAAAAUAAUAGAAAAGAUGGUCUUAAACAAAAGCUGUUCAGUGCUGCUGCUCACCAAAUGCACAAACCUAAGACCCAUGGAAAUCUUUCUACCAGCCUAUUUCUUCCUCCUUCCCCACUUUCUUUAACUAAAAGAGAAAUUUAUGAAUUAAUUUCAGUGGAGAAGUAGAUGGUUUUUUAACCAUCAAAUACAUUAUAAUUUUACUAGAAAAAGUAUAAGCAUUAUACAUAUGGAUAUAAAGAAAAAAUAAUUAUGUGCAAAUGCAAGAAUAUUGGCAGUAUGUUGUGUUUGACAGUAACUCUUUGAUAAAGUCAACUAACAGCACAAUUUUUUAAAAAUAGGUGUAGUUUUAAAAUGCAGUUGUUUGGAUCUUUUUUUUUUUUUUUUUUUUAGUUAUUAAAUGUUUUAUCCUUGUGUCAGUUAAGCAGGUGAUAAUGCUUUACAGGUUAUAUAGUACUUUCAGAGAAACUUUACUUAAAUCUCAAAAUAGUCCAAUAAGAAGAUAACCCUGUUUUAUAGGUACAGAAAUUGAGGCUUAAAAAAAAAUUAAGUGAGUUGUUCUAGGUCAGAUGUUAGUAAGUGGCAGAAUGGUAAUCUAAACCCAAGGCCUCAACAACUACAAAAAAUCUGAAAGUCUGUUUUUUUCCUAGAGUUUAGCUACUUUAUCCUGACCCUUCUCAAUCAGUAGUCUGUCUUCAACGAUUUGGACUUCAAACCACUUUUAGAAAUAUGUCUGUGAACUCAUGUGCGUAUCCAGAGCUUUACAAGUCAGCAAGAGAAUGCCUCAGAAUAGAUUUUCCAAUAUGUAGCAACAUAAGCCUAAAGAAUAAUUUUCAAGAUUAUCUCUAUAUUUUUAUUUUAAGUAAAAGUACAUGACAGAUCCUGGAUUAAUGAGAAAGGGAUCAAAUAUUAAUCCAAAAUGGAAGCUAUUUUAAUUUAGACAUUUGGUGGUAUUUAAUUUGAUAUACAAGGAGGUUAGAAGGAGAAAUAGGUUUUACAAUAGAGAUAAGUUUUUCUUAUACCUGCUGAGUGUUUUAUUUUAAGUAGGAUUUUUUUGGCCAGUUAAUCCAUGCUAAUAGGAAAUUUGGAAAAUAGAGAAAAAUAUAAAAAAUGUAAAAUAAGAGUCCCUUAUUUCAUUAACAUCGUAAUAAGAGAUAAGCACUUUUAAUUAUUUAUGGCCUUCUAGUCUUUUAAUCAGUGUCUGUAUUUAAUGUAAUUGGGAUGAUAAUUUAUGCAUUUUUGUUUUUUUUGUUUUGUUUAACCCUGAUUCCAGUUUCUACAUGAUUAUUUUUACGACAUAUUUUUGUUAGCUACAUAACGUUCUAGUGUCAGAAUUAUUAGUAUUUAGUUAAAACCUGCUCAGAUUGGGUUUUUAGGUUGUGUUUUUGCUGCAAUAAACAUAAUAGGAACAACAUGUUUUCAUGUAAAGCUUUAUCCUCAUUUUGUACUGCAGGAAAAAUACCUAGGUUAGAAUUACUAAAUUAAAAAAUGGACACUUGGGGCCAGGCGCAGUGGCUUACGCCUGUAAUUCCACCACUUUGGGGAGCUGAGGCGGGCAGAUCACUUGACAUCGAGAGUUCAAGACCAGCCUGACCAACAUGGAGAAACCCCGUCUCUACUAAAAAUACAAAAAAUUAUCCAGACGUAGUGGCACAUGCCUGUAAUCUCAGCUACUUGGGAGGCUGAGGUAGGAGAAUCGCUUGAACCCGGGAGGCAGAGGUUGUGGUGAGCCGAGAUCAUGCCAUUGAACUCCAGCCUGGGCAACAAGAGCGAAACUCCGUCUCCAAAAAAAAAAAAAGACACUUAUUUAGGCUUUCCAUAUAUCAUGGUAAUUUGCUUUCUAAAAGGCUAUAUGAAUUUUUAAGUGUGCUUGUUUCUCUAUAUGCUCAACAGAAUGGAAUGCUAUCUUAAAAGAAAAAAGAUACUUGGUAGUUUGAUAACUAGUAAUGUUAUUUUAAGUUGUAUGUUUUUAGUUACUAGUAAGCAGUUUGAAUUCUGUGAAACUUUUGUUCAUGAUCUUUACUCAUUUUUUAAGUGCAUUUAUGAUCUCUUCAGGCUAUUAGCCUCUUGUCAUCAAAUGUGUGUAAGAUUUAAGACUCAUCACUGUCAAGUUAAUGGAUGAGUUCUCAGAGGCAAAGGCUUUAUAGAGAAAAGAAGAUAGGAGUGUGAACUGAGCCCUGAGGACAGCCUGCAAGGAGUGGAUAAAAAGCCAAUAAACAGAAAAUGUUAGUGUUCAGAAAUUAGGAGAAGACUGAAUACUUUCCCUACUCUUAAAAUUAAUCCUUUUAUUAUAAGUAUACAGUCUUUUCUCUCAGAAUUUAGUUAAGUAACUCACUGAUGUUACUCAAAAAUUGUUACUCGAUUAAAAAAAUUUUCUGAGCUAAGAUGACAGUGACUGUCUUCUAAAUUUUAGUUUCAGUUAAUUUUUCAAAACAAAACCAACACAAUCAAAGCCCCCUUGUGCACCUCUGACUGUAUCCCUCCCUGCCUUCCAAUUAUCCUGAAAUUGAUAUUUAUCACUCCCAUCUUUUGUACGUGUGUCUCACAUCCUGUACCUUAGUCUUUUCUUGUUAAUUAAAGCAGAUGUUCCAUGUAAACUUAUUUAUUAAUAUUUCUUCAACUGAAAUAUCAUUUGGACCUAGGGUAAAGUUAAAUAUACUAUUGUGUUAUAUUACUCCGUUUACUUUCUUCUAUGUUUGCCUUUGAAUUGUCCAACUCUUUGCUAGUUCCAUGCUUGGUUUAACCCAGCCAGUGUUCUGCCGUCUGUGGUUAGUAGAACUCAGAAAUUGGAGGAAUCCAGAACAGUAGUUGAAAUACUUGGGGGCGGGGGACAGGGUAGGAGUGGAGGGUAGGAGCAAGAGGGCAAAGAGAAAUGAAAUGCAGCUGAGAGAAUAAUCAGAUUCCUUCCAAAGCAACUGAACAUUGUCAGUCCGCAUAGCAUCAUAAAUAGCUUUCUGAAACUACUUUUUUUUUUUUUUUUGAGACGGAGCCUUGCUCUGCUGCUCAGGCUGGAGUGCGGUGGCGCGAUCUCGGCUCACUGCAACCUCUGCCUCCCAGGUUCAGGCGAUUCUCCUGCCUAAGCCUCCCGAGUAGCUGGGACUACCAGCGUGCGCCACCACGCCCAGCUAAUUUUUGUGUUCUUAGUAGAGAUGGGGUUUUACCAUGUUGGCCAGGAUGGUCUCGAUCUCUUGACCUCGUGAUCUCCUUGCCUUAGCCUCCCAAAGUGCUGGGAUUACAGGCAUGAACCACCACACCCGGCCAGAAACUACUUUUUACGGCUGGAGUUUCAGAACUAAUUUAGUAAAGGAUUGAAAAGGAAGGAGGAUACAGUUGACUCAUUUGUACAGAGUAUAUGACUCAUUUGUACAGAAUGAAAACAUGUUUAUGAAGGUUCACACUAAGUGAAAGCUGGCAUCCAAGUUGAUUCAGACAAAAGUGAAAGUCAAGAAGUUAAUAGUACAUUAAUUCUCCAAAUGCAUGCCAGCAGAGCGUGGCAGGAAGGUACACAAGUCAGCAGAUCUGGGUUGUCCUGGUUCUCCUAUUGACUCGUGUGUGUGAUGUUAGGGAAGACAUGUAAGGAAUUUGCAUAAGACAGUUAUGCAAAAUGGAGCUGGAGGAGCUUUAUUUGUGCACAGAGAUACUCCUGAGAAUAACCCUGAUACUCCAUUUGAUUUCACACCAGAAAACUAUAAGAGGAUAGAGGCAAUUGUAAAAAACUAUCCAGAAGGCCAUAAAGCAGCAGCUGUUCUUCCAGUCCUGGAUUUAGCCCAAAGGCAGAAUGGGUGGUUGCCCAUCUCUGCUAUGAACAAGGUUGCAGAAGUUUUACAAGUACCUCCAAUGAGAGUAUAUGAAGUAGCAACUUUUUAUACAAUGUAUAAUCGAAAGCCAGUUGGAAAGUAUCACAUUCAGGUCUGCACUACUACACCCUGCAUGCUUCGAAACUCUGACAGCAUACUGGAGGCCAUUCAGAAAAAGCUUGGAAUAAAGGUUGGGGAGACUACACCUGACAAACUUUUCACUCUUAUAGAAGUGGAAUGUUUAGGGGCCUGUGUGAACGCACCAAUGGUUCAAAUAAAUGACAAUUACUAUGAGGAUUUGACAGCUAAGGAUAUUGAAGAAAUUAUUGAUGAGCUCAAGGCUGGCAAAAUCCCAAAACCAGGGCCAAGGAGUGGACGCUUCUCUUGUGAGCCAGCUGGAGGUCUUACCUCUUUGACUGAACCACCCAAGGGACCUGGAUUUGGUGUACAAGCAGGCCUUUAAUUUAUAUUGAACUGUAAAUAUGUCACUAGAGAAAUAAAAUAUGGACUUCCAAUCUACGUAAA